GCCAGUUGAGAAGGACUCUGAUCCGGCUCAGCUUUCCAAUCAGCUGCGGAAGGAGCCACGCUUUCGGGGGUUGCAAGAUGGCGGCCACCAGUGGAACUGAUGAGCCGGUUUCCGGGGAGUUGGUGUCUGUGGCACAUGCGCUUUCUCUCCCAGCAGAGUCGUAUGGCAACGAUCCUGACAUUGAGAUGGCUUGGGCCAUGAGAGCAAUGCAGCAUGCUGAAGUCUAUUACAAGCUGAUUUCAUCAGUUGACCCACAGUUCCUGAAACUCACCAAAGUAGAUGACCAAAUUUACUCUGAGUUCCGGAAAAAUUUUGAGACCCUUAGGAUAGAUGUGUUGGACCCAGAAGAACUCAAGUCAGAAUCAGCCAAAGAGAAGUGGAGGCCAUUCUGCUUGAAGUUUAAUGGGAUUGUUGAAGACUUCAACUAUGGUACUUUGCUGCGACUAGAUUGUUCUCAGGGCUACACUGAGGAAAACACCAUCUUUGCCCCCAGGAUACAAUUCUUUGCCAUUGAAAUUGCUCGGAACCGGGAAGGCUAUAACAAAGCUGUUUAUAUCAGUGUUCAGGACAAAGAAGGAGAGAAAGGAGUCAACAAUGGAGGAGAAAAAAGAGCUGACAGUGGAGAAGAAGAGAACACCAAGAAUGGAGGAGAGAAAGGAGCUGAUAGUGGAGAAGAAAAAGAGGAAGGAAUCAACAGAGAAGACAAAACUGACAAAGGAGGAGAAAAAGGGAAAGAAGCUGACAAAGAAAUCAACAAAAGUGGUGAAAAAGCUAUGUAAGGUAUACAGGGAACAGCACUCUAGAAGCUAUGACUCAAUUGAGACUACAAGUACCACGGUGCUACUUGCACAGACCCCUUUGGUUAAAUGUAAAUUCUUGUACAAUUGAAGGAUACGCAGAAGGACAUCUUUCUAGUCUAACAGUCAGGAGCUGCUCUGGUCAUUCCCUUGUAUGAACUGGUCUAAAGACUGUUAGUGGGGUGUUAGUUGAUUUUUCCUGGUAUACUGUUUCUUGGCUGACACUACUGGUCAAGUAAGAAAUUUGUAAAUAAAUUUCUUUUGGUUCUUAUUAUCUAUAUCUGUGACUGACUUUAAAAAGGUAUUUGACACUUGAAAUUUUUUUCAAAUAUGUAAUCUCAUCACCAUGUCUUAUAUAAGAUAAUUUACUCCUGUUUCUUACUGCUUC